AGAGCAGCGGAUCCCGGUCUCGCCGCAGCAGCAGCGCGGGUGUCGUGCACCGCCUGAAGACGCCGUACCUUUCUACCCCCCACCUUUUUUUUUUUUUUUUUUAAAUAACCGGAACCAAUGAACGCAGCCGGGAUCAGAGCUCCGGAGGCCGCCGGUGCCGAUGGGACCAGGCUGGCGCCCGGCGGGAGCCCGUGUCUGAGGCGGCGGGGGCGGCCGGAGGAGUCGCCGGCGGCGGUGGUGGCGCCUCGCGGAGCCGGCGAGCUGCAGGCGGCCGGGGCGCCGCUGCGCUUUCACCCGGCUUCUCCUCGGCGCCUUCAUCCCGCCUCGACUCCUGGCCCAGCGUGGGGCUGGCUGCUGCGGCGGCGGCGCUGGGCUGCGUUGCUGGUGCUCGGGCUGCUGGUAGCCGGAGCGGCGGACGGAUGCGAGCUUGUGCCCCGGCACCUCCGCGGGCGGCGGGCGACUGGCUCUGCCGCAACUGCCGCCUCCUCUCCCGCCGCGGCGGCCGGCGAUAGCCCGGCGCUCAUGACAGAUCCCUGCAUGUCACUGAGUCCACCAUGCUUUACAGAAGAAGACAGAUUUAGUCUGGAAGCUCUUCAAACAAUACAUAAACAAAUGGAUGAUGACAAAGAUGGUGGAAUUGAAGUAGAGGAAAGUGAUGAAUUCAUCAGAGAAGAUAUGAAAUAUAAAGAUGCUACUAAUAAACACAGCCAUCUGCACAGAGAAGAUAAACAUAUAACGAUUGAGGAUUUAUGGAAACGAUGGAAAACAUCAGAAGUUCAUAAUUGGACCCUUGAAGACACUCUUCAGUGGUUGAUAGAGUUUGUUGAACUACCCCAAUAUGAGAAGAAUUUUAGAGACAACAAUGUCAAAGGAACGACACUUCCCAGGAUAGCAGUGCACGAACCUUCAUUUAUGAUCUCCCAGUUGAAAAUCAGUGACCGGAGUCACAGACAAAAACUUCAGCUCAAGGCAUUGGAUGUGGUUUUGUUUGGACCUCUAACACGCCCACCUCAUAACUGGAUGAAAGAUUUUAUCCUCACAGUUUCUAUAGUAAUUGGUGUUGGAGGCUGCUGGUUUGCUUAUACGCAGAAUAAGACAUCAAAAGAACAUGUUGCAAAAAUGAUGAAAGAUUUAGAGAGCUUACAAACUGCAGAGCAAAGUCUAAUGGACUUACAGGAGAGGCUUGAAAAGGCACAGGAAGAAAACAGAAAUGUUGCUGUAGAAAAGCAAAAUUUAGAGCGCAAAAUGAUGGAUGAAAUCAAUUAUGCAAAGGAGGAGGCUUGUCGGCUGAGAGAGCUAAGGGAGGGAGCUGAAUGUGAAUUGAGUAGACGUCAGUAUGCAGAACAGGAAUUGGAACAGGUUCGCAUGGCUCUGAAAAAGGCCGAAAAAGAAUUUGAACUGAGAAGCAGUUGGUCUGUUCCAGAUGCACUUCAGAAAUGGCUUCAGUUAACACAUGAAGUAGAAGUGCAAUACUACAAUAUUAAAAGACAAAACGCUGAAAUGCAGCUAGCUAUUGCUAAAGAUGAGGCAGAAAAAAUUAAAAAGAAGAGAAGCACAGUCUUUGGGACUCUGCACGUUGCACACAGCUCCUCCCUAGAUGAGGUAGACCACAAAAUUCUGGAAGCAAAGAAAGCUCUCUCUGAGUUGACAACUUGUUUACGAGAACGACUUUUUCGCUGGCAACAAAUUGAGAAGAUCUGUGGCUUUCAGAUAGCCCAUAACUCAGGACUCCCCAGCCUGACCUCUUCCCUUUAUUCUGAUCACAGCUGGGUGGUGAUGCCCAGAGUCUCCAUUCCACCCUAUCCAAUUGCUGGAGGAGUUGAUGACUUAGAUGAAGACACACCCCCAAUAGUGUCACAAUUUCCCGGGACCAUGGCUAAACCUCCUGGAUCAUUAGCCAGAAGCAGCAGCCUGUGCCGUUCACGCCGCAGCAUUGUGCCGUCCUCGCCUCAGCCUCAGCGAGCUCAGCUUGCUCCACACGCCCCCCACCCGUCACACCCUCGGCACCCUCACCACCCGCAACACACACCACACUCCUUGCCUUCCCCUGAUCCAGAUAUCCUCUCAGUGUCAAGUUGCCCUGCGCUUUAUCGAAAUGAAGAGGAGGAAGAGGCCAUUUACUUCUCUGCUGAAAAGCAAUGUAUUCACCUUGGGCUCGGUGCGUGCAAAAGUGAAUGAGACUAAGUAGUAAAGCUCUCAAAAAAAAAAAGGAAGUGCCAGACACAGCUUCAGAAUGUGACUCCUUAAAUUCUUCCAUUGGAAGGAAACAGUCUCCUCCUUUAAGCCUCGAGAUAUACCAAACAUUAUCUCCGCGAAAGAUAUCAAGAGAUGAGGUGUCCCUAGAGGAUUCCUCCCGAGGGGAUUCGCCUGUAACUGUGGAUGUGUCUUGGGGUUCUCCCGACUGUGUAGGUCUGACAGAAACUAAGAGUAUGAUCUUCAGUCCUGCAAGCAAAGUGUACAAUGGCAUUUUGGAGAAAUCCUGUAGCAUGAACCAGCUUUCCAGUGGCAUCCCGGUGCCUAAACCUCGCCACACAUCAUGUUCCUCAGCUGGCAACGACAGUAAACCAGUUCAGGAAGCCCCAAGUGUUGCCAGAAUAAGCAGCAUCCCACAUGACCUUUGUCAUAAUGGAGAGAAAAGCAAAAAGCCAUCAAAAAUCAAAAGCCUUUUUAAGAAGAAAUCUAAGUGAACUGGCUGACUUGAUGGAAUCAUGUUCAAGUGGCAUCUGUAAACUAUUAUCCCCCACCCUCCACUCCCCACCUUUUUUUUGGUUUAAUUUUAGGAAUGUAACUCCAUUGGGGCUUUCCAGGCCGGAUGCCAUAGUGGAACAUCCAGAAGGGCAACUGUCUACUGUCUGCUUAUUUAAGUGACUAUAUAUAAUCAAUUCAUCAAGCCAGUUAUUACUGAAAAAUCAUUGAAAUGAGACAGUUUACAGUCAUUUCUGCCUAUUUAUUUCUGCUUUGUUCUCAGUGAUGUAUAUGCAACAUUUUGUUGAAAGCCACGAUGGACUUACAAGCUUUAAUGGACUCGUAAGCCAGCAUGGGCUUGCAAAAAUUUCUUGUUUACCAGAGCAUCUUCUUAUCUUUCCACAGAGCUAUUUACAUCCUGGACUAUAUAACUUAAAAGAAGUAAAACGUAAUUGCACUACUGUUUUCCAGACUGGAAAAAAAAAAAAUCUCUGCAAGUGAAACUGUAUAGAGUUUAUAAAAUGACUAUGGAUAGGGGACUGUUUUCACUUUUAGAUCAAAAUGGGUUUUUAAGUAGAACCUAGGGUUUCUAAUUGACUUGAUUUCUGGAAAUGAAAACCCGCGCUUUUAUUAUGGGAAGCUUCUUGAACUGCAUUUACUAUUGUGAAGUUUCAAGUCCCGCUGUAAAGAUCAUGUUGUUUUGUUUUCCCCAGGGCUUUCACUGUGAUUUACUGCAUUGCAGGCUGUAUGAUAAAACACACAUAAUUUAAAGAGAGAAGGCUCUUGAUUCCUUAUGCAAGUGGAAGAGUUGAAACUUGAUUGAAGGACUUAAAACAUUCACAACCUUAAGCCGAGGUGGGGGGAUAUGGGGAUUCAGGCAAUUGUUUACACACUUUGAAUAACUGCAAAGGAUUUACGGUUUGUGAAAAAUGUGUACUGUGGAAAAGAUAAUAAAUUGAAGACAUUAUUGUGUGGGAUUGUGCUGAUUUUUGUUGAUAACACAAAAAACACUAUGUUUUCUGGAGAGCUGUGUAAGCUGUCUUGUUGCUUAGUUGCAAUAUAAGAAAUAGUGAUGUUUUGGACGUAAGUUGUCAACAAAUUUCUAUUUUAUAUUGUUAUAUUUUUAUGUAGUUUGAAAUGUAAAAAUGUUCUAAUAUCAAGAUUAACAAAUAUAAAUUUAUGGUGCAUUUAGAUUGCGUUGUAUUAAUUUAUAAAGUAUGGUGUUCAUUAAAUUGGUGGGUUGUAUAAGGGUAGCUUUUGUUGUUAAAAAAACAGUAGAGAGUUAAGUUCCAUAUAGCAACAAAGUAUGUUAACAUCUAGGGAGUUUCUGCUUAUACCACUUUAAAAAUAUGCAAUCAUAAGUGAUUUGGUUACUGCAAUGCAGAUGGAUGUUUGGAUGAACAACUGAUACAUUUUAGUUAGAAUGCUUUUUCAGCAUUAUGGCUAAAAUAUAUGUCUAACCCAGUGCUAUUUAGGUGAAAAUGCUAAUUGAUAAACCAGAAGUUUCUUUUGAGAUUUGCUUUAAAGAAAUGCUUUAGUAAGAAUAUGAACAAUUUCCUGAUGUCUCCUAUAAAUUGUGAUUGUUUAUUCUAUUACUAUUGUUAAAAACUUGAAUGGUAUUUAUAUUGGCUGAUAUUUAUAUACUUAAUAGAUUGAGUUCUGUAAGGGCAAAAACGGAUUGAAAUGAACAUAGCGUUUUGCACUAAUGAUAAGAUAACCUGAGAGGUAGGGUUGAGGAACACAGGGUUGAAAGCUGUUGGAGAGGGGAAAAGUUGUGCAUAAAGAACUGAAAAGGGUUCUGGAGUGUUCAUUCAGAGUGAAGGGAAAACUUUAUCCUUCUAUUUCUUAUAACCAGACAGGAGGAGUUCUUCCCUUUGAAAAUUGCAAAAGGAAUGAGAACUUUGCAGUUGGAUGAAUAGAGAAGGGAAAAGUUGCUGGAGCACGGAGUGAAGAUGGGAGGAGCUGUUAGCAAGGCCCACUGCUGCUCCUGGGUGAGAAGGGAGCUCUGGAGCAGGACCAGCUGGGGGCCGGCACUGCUGCUUAGAGUGGAGGAGGCUGGCCAAAGAGACUGUGGGCUGUUUUCAGUCAGGGAGCAUGUGCAUUGUUUGUGCUCAAUUUCAGACACUCAUUUAUAAACAAAUUCAACCAAGGGAUAUUUACUGCUUUAUGUUGCUUAUGAUAAUUAUUUUGCAUUAAUACAGUAUACACAUUUGUAAAUUCAACAGGAAAUUAUUGAGUUUUGGAAAGCUACAGUAAUUUCUGUAUUACAUCAUUUAUAUGUGAAAAGUUGGACAUUUCUGUAAGUUUUUAAAAUUAUCCAUUUGUUACUUUAACAUUUUAAAAUUAUGGUGUUUUCCUGAUUUUAAAAGCAAUAUUUUCCUUACUGU